AGGUAAAACUUCCUUUUCCUGUAGAUCAAAUCACAGAUCUUCCAAGGAACGAUUUCCAGAUGAUGAUUAAAAUGCACAAGCUAACCUCAGAACAGUUAGAGUUUAUUCAUGAUGUCCGACGGCGCAGCAAGAACCGCAUCGCGGCCCAGCGCUGCCGCAAAAGGAAACUGGACUGUAUUCAGAAUUUAGAAUGUGAAAUCCGCAAAUUGGUGUGUGAGAAAGAGAAACUGUUGUCAGAGAGGAAUCAACUGAAAGCAUGCAUGGGGGAACUGUUGGACAACUUCUCCUGCCUUUCCCAGGAAGUUUGCCGAGACAUCCAGAGCCCCGAGCAGAUCCAGGCCCUGCAUCGGUAUUGCCCUGUCCUCAGACCCAUGGACUUGCCCACGGCCUCCAGUAUUAACCCUGCGCCCUUGGGUGCUGAGCAGAACAUUGCGGCCUCCCAAUGCGCAGUGGGGGAAAACGUGCCCUGCUGCUUGGAGCCAGGCGCGGCUCCCCCCGGACCCCCCUGGGCACCCAGCAACACCUCCGAGAAUUGUACCUCUGGGAGGAGACUAGAAGGCACUGACCCGGGAACCUUCUCAGAGAGAGGACCUCCUCUUGAACCCAGGAGCCAAACAGUGACCGUGGACUUCUGCCAGGAAAUGACUGAUAAGUGUACAACUGACGAACAGCCCAGGAAAGAUUAUACCUAGUGACUCGGCUCUGCCUCCCAGUCCGCACACCUCUCCCAUCCAGGCGUUCUUCAGUCAGCCUGUGGCACUGUUCAUCUGCUGUCCCGAAGAAACCGAGAACACAUUUGGUGCACACUACAGCGGUCUUAGCAGCAAUACUGUUCCGAAGUAUCCUCUCCUCUUCUCGAGCAGGAGUGAUAGUUACCUUCACAAUGGUGCUACCCCUUGCCCAGGCAAGGAAAGACAGCAGUGAUGACACUGUCUGUCUGUGGCUCAAUUUCAGUCUUCACAGGGAUAGACUACAACACCUCUAGGCCCCAACCACGGAUUUUUUUUCUCAGUGGCCCAUGUCACAAACCCUAUCUCAGGAAUUUCUUCUGAAUGUUCAAUUUUUUUCAUUGAAGACAGCUUCUAUACACAUCAAAGUUUUAUAGCUAGACUGUACAUAUUAUAUAUAAUAUAUAUAUAAAAUAUAUAUAUAUAUAUAUAUAUAUCCAUAUGCAAAAGUCCUGCAUGCCUCAACUUUCUCAUCCUAAAACUGGAAACUUAUUUCUCAUUUAGAAACAGGUUCCAACAUUCCUCUUCUUUUGUCUCUGAUGCUAGAACUAGUUUGGUAACUGUUAACAUGGUCAUUUUUCUUGCUUCACAGUUCAAUUUUCAAUUCGUACUUAUUUAUGGACAAAAUUCAGUGUUGGAAGCUUUUUCCCAAGGUUUUAUUUCAGAUUUCUUUUUCGUUUGGUUUGGUUUUGGCACCUCCAAGUGGUGUCAUUUGAGCAUUGUAGGUUUGUUUUUUGUUUGUUUGGGGGGUUUUGUUUGUUUUUGUUUUUGUUUUUGUUUUCCUUGCAGAUACUGUACAGUAAUGGUCAACUUUGCCACUUGCACUGAGUUUUGGGUCAAACCUAUUUUCUUAAAUGAAGUUGUAACUUCGGUAUAACUCAAGUAUACUGUAUAUUCUUUGCUUUUAGUUAAAAAAGUAAAACAUUUUAGCUAAUUAAAAAGCACUCAGGUGAUAAUUAUGUAGGAAAAACAAUCUUGCCAAAUAAUGAAUUCAUCCUAGGAUGUGUAGACAAUAAUCUGCUUGAAUAUUUUUAUAUUUCACCUCCUCCCCACCUUUCCCUAAGCAAAGUUUAAACGCAGAUAGAGAGUUCAGAGUUGAUGCUGGAUGUUCAGAUUCCUAAGUGGGGAGAGAGUUUGGACAUCUCACUCAAAAGUACAUCAGAAAAACAGGAAUCCGUGAUUUUAUACCAGAACUCAGCAGGCAUUGGCUCCUAGAAAUCAAGUUAGAAAGUUUUCACCCAGGGAGUAAGUCCCAUUCAUUUCAACACGUCCUGAGGCCUCGGCUUGCUCUUGGAAGUGUUGUGCAGUAGGACCUGCUCCCCUGAAGGACGGGGCCAACCAGCCACUGGCUUUCCUGCCCAGGCUUGGCCUCCCAGGACAUCUGGCCUGAGGGGAUUUGAAUCACAGCCCCGAAGGUCCUGCCUUCACCCCAUUGGGAGAGAGCAGGGCAUCCUGGCAUCUGCGAUCCAUCCCUGACACAGGCUGACACAUUCUUUCUCCUUUCCUUCUCCAAAGGCUUGGAGUUUUCUUCUGAGGUUUUUCUGCCAGUGUCUUGUCUGAAGGCAGACUUCAUUCUGAGGCUUUGGACAAGCUAUCACCGGGAACCCUCCCUGUCCCCUUCCCGAAUCACACACAUACCCUACCCUCACCUGAUGAUAAUUUUCUCUUCUUGCUGCAAAACUGGUUGGCUUGCAACCCAGAGAGAGCAGCUUCCCUUGGCUCUGGGGCCGUGUUGGCCCCAGCCACGUUUACAGGAAGGUGUGCCCCAGAGGAGGAGGAAUCAGCUCCCUCGCUCCAGUGGCCUUGGGUCCGGGUCUCACUGAGCAGCCCGAGGGCCACUCCAGCCCGGCUGGGGAAGAGAGUCCUGAACGGUUUGAUGUGGGGAUGGGGUGGUGGGCAGUGGGGAAUAGAUGGUUGACUUUGUUUCUUUAUUUGUGCCAUUGUUUGGACAAUAUUAAAGCUGCAUGUAAAAGGGGAAAUUAGUAUAUGAUGUAGGCUAAAAGUGAAAUCAUAGUAACAUAUGUUUUAGUAUUAUUAACUUUUUUCUGUACAAAUAUUAGCACUAAAUGUUUAAAUAUGUAUGAAUGCCAGAAAUUUGUCAGUUCAUGCAGUAGGAUAAAAAAAAAAAAAAAAAAAAAAAAAAGGCUUUUCUUUUUAAACAGUUCCACUUUUAAAACCUGCCUCUGGGUUUUUGUUUUUUCUUGUUUGUGUGUGUGUGUGUGUGUGUGUGUGUGUGUGUGUGUGUGUGUGUGUGUGUCUGAAACAGAUCUUGAUAAAGCUCUGUGUUGGAGCUGCUGGUUUUUGUUAUGGUUGUUGGAAUUUCUUGGCCUACUAGGACAGUUCUGUGCUUCACCAUGAGGUUUGCCUUUGUGGAAAACUGGUGACAGUGAGAAUAUAAACUCAAUGUGAAUCACGUGAUACUUCGCAGGCGUGUGUUACAGUGGAGUCAGCUGACAGUAUUUUGCUUUUUAACUCUAUUGUUGCCUUUCCAAGUGACCUCUCCUCUUCUUUUAAAAAAAGAACACUUUCUGCUCAUAUCAUAACCAGGUCCAACCCAGCUUCUUGGCAUGAGGUUUACCCUGGUAACAACUCAUGUGCAACUGGUAGUCUUGACCACAUUCCAUCCAUUUCCUCAGGUUUCUGUGGUUCAGUAGCCCAGACCUGUUUGGCAGCCAUUUCUAGCAGGGGCGGGGCCUCUUUAUUUCUCUCCACCCUAACUCAGACCUCACCUUCCUCCCACCCACCCCUGCCUUGCUUUUCUUCCUCUUCCCCCAACCUAACUUCUGCCAUGGGAACUGGUUAAAAACACUGCUCUAAAAACCAUCUUCCAAUUUCAUAGAGAUUUCUCACAAGUUAUUUCAUUCAUAAUCCACCAUGAACAGUGACUAGCUUCGUGCAGUUGUUCAUGUGAUGUGUGUGUGUCUUUUCCUAUUCAGAACUAUGUGCUUGUCAAAAUUAUUUCUGGGUUGAUUCAAAGGGAGGACUUGCUGGGGACCAGAAUCCAAACGGCCUCAAGUGGAAUUUUAAAACCUAGCCUGUCUCUUUUCCCUGGGAUCCCUCUGUCAACCCCACGCCUUUUAGGAAAAAGAAAAGUGAGUGAACAGCAAGGAAGAGUGUUUGCACAGUACAGUAACAUUUGGUUGUUCUUAAGGCUCUUUUCUUACAAAAAUAAGAGACCCUCCAACCACGGGCUGUUUAGGAGGAUGCCUGCUUGGGUCUCCAAAUGGCUGGGGUAGGAAUGGUUGUUGGGGCAGAGCCAGUGGAGGUGAGUGACCCUGAGACUAAUGAACAUCCCACCUAAAUCCAGUCCUCCCCUUGGAUCUGCCUUUGUCCUGCUUGUGUAUCCAGGCAACCUCUUUUCAAGUUGGUCAGGCUUUGGACAGGUGAGUGAUUUGCUGUAUGUGUUUGUUUCUCUGCGUUACCUGGGGGUGCCUUGAUUAAAAUCGAACUUUAUUACAUACUGAUUCUGGAACAAAACAGUUAGAAAAACUUUAAAAAAAAAAAAACCGACAAAGUUACGAGGCCAUCCUGCUAUUUAUCUUCUGAGUUCCCAGCAAUGACUCAGGCAUCAGAGAUGAUGCUGCAGUGGAAAACCUGACUCUGUGUGUCUGCAACUGAAUGUUGUGCGAGUAAUUUAUUAACUGUCUUUCUAAAGGUUUGCUGCUUUUAAGAUGCACUAUAAUUCGGGAUGUAAUCCUUACAUUGCUUUUCCAAGGAAGGGAACAAAAGUCUAGUGAUUAGUAUGCCAACUGCCACUACUCCUUCAAAAGGAGCCAGGACCAGCGACAAGACUCAUGAGAGGACUGGCUAAAGUGAAGUGUGCACAGUGUGAAGUUUAAUGCUGUUGUCAAGAGGCCUAAACCCACAUUUUCUCUUUUAAUAUUUUAUGAUUGCCAUCAAAGAAGAAGAAAAAGAAGGAACAGACAAAGGUUUGAAAAUGAUAAGCCUGUUAAGACACCAAAAACUCCUGUCCCGUGAAGCUGCUUGACAUCCUGUGGAGUAGCAUAAUCCUCUCAAAAUGAGGAAGAGCUGCCUGCAAAGCUUUCUCAAGUCCCUAUUUGGCUACCUACUUCUCUACAUUAUGCCCCAUUUAAACUAGGAGCUGUCUUAGAAAUGACUUCAAACUGCUUCACUAUUGCUUACAGUUUAGGAGGAGUCUCAGAUCCAGAAGGAGCAAGAAUCAAGUUUGGUCCUCAAAUGACUGUAAAUAGACUAAAGAACAAGGUGUUUUUUGUUUUUGUUUUUGUUUUCUAAGAAUAAAGCUGUUCGUUGUAUCAUGAGUUAGUGUUUCUUCCCCAAACUGAAGACUGUGUUGGAAGUGCAAUUUCUGGUGAGUCAGUCCACAAUACAAUGCCCUGUGUGGAGUUGGUAUUCAUACAGGAAAUCUGUGUGCACGAGGCAUUGUGUGUUGAAAGUGUAUGUUUAUAGUACUGCCUGAGCCAUCUCAUGACCCCAGCGUCCAAAACCGAUGCUGUAGAACAGAACAUAUCUGUACACAAAUAGUGUGUGCAAAUAGCAUUUGUACAUAGAAAAGUCUCAUUGUGGCAGAUUGAGCAUAAAUUAUUCAACUGACGGUGCAAAAACAUUACUUGCAAAGAAAAGUUUAUAGUAUUUUCCUACACUCCACCCUGGGAGAUGAUAUUUCUAUCAAAUGAAUAUCAGUGCAUUUUAAAUGUAAUAUGAAAACGAUGCUGCCAUUUUGUGAAGAAUACCCACUUGGUUGCAGAGGCCAACUUUCAUAGCUUUGAUUUAAUGUUGUGACACGGUGUAUGCAUUUUGCUGUCAAGCAAUGGAUAAACAGCUCUGACUUUCAUUCUCAUUCCAGUUUAUUGACCUCAGAUAAAACACUGGCCCUUCUUAGAAGCAGAAGUGUGCACCAAGACCAUUCAUUUCAGGUAGACUCACAUUCAGUGCCAAGUGCUCCCAUGGGAAUAAUCAGACGCAUAUGUUGCGAAAGAGUGAAGGGACUUGGACAAAGAGGGGUUUUCCUACAGAUGGAUGCUCAGUCUUCUACCAAAACAUGUUUGGAGGCAGAACUAUGACCUCCCCUUAAGUCCUAACAAUGUAUUUUGUGUGUGCAAAUCCUGGGAUGCCCGUUUCACGCUCUGACAUAAAGACAUGGCACCUCUAGUGAGUGAUCAGGAAGAUUCCAUAUGCAUUUGGGAGCUUCAGGUGCUUGUUAGACACAGUGAGCCAUUCAAGGCAAGCACCACCUUUGCUAGUGAGGCCAAGAGAGCCUGUGACAAUUUGACAAUUUGUUCCAGAACCAGUCUGAUGCAAGUGCACCUCUAAUAUAUGCCUUACAAACUCCAGAGGCCAUAUUCAAAACAGGGUCUUCUCAGUGUAUGCAAGGGGCUGCAGCCCCUCUUCUCUUCCUCCCCAGGUUGAACAAUACGGACAGUUUUCACACAUAUCUACCUGUAUAACCCUCUGUACCUCUCAUAACUGGUCAACGACUGUAACAGGUUACAUCAGGUGUUUUUCUACAUACUUUUUACACAGAUUCUAUGCGAUUAAUGUAAUUUAAUUCAAUGCAUCAUUUUAUUGUACUAGUUCUUAGGCUUGUCCUUAUUUUUUUCUAAGUGAUUGUGGUUUUUCUCGUGGUUUUUAUUGUAAAAAAUGAAAGGCUGUUGAUGCUUAUUCUCUGUAACUAAGAAUUUUUACCUUUUGGGGGAAAAAAGCAUUGCUAUGAACUAAUGAAUUGAAACUUCAUUUACUCAUUGUAAAUACACUAUUGUGCAAAAAAAGUUUUCACUCAAUUGAAUUGCUAGUGUUAACUGAAUUUUGUCUAGACACCAUUUCUGUUGAUGAAAUAAAGACAUAUCAUUAUGCAUUGUAAACUGA